AGACUCAGCUCCUGGUGAAGCUCCCAGCCAUCAGCCAUGAGGGUCUUGUAUCUCCUCUUCUCGUUCCUCUUCAUAUUUCUGAUGCCUCUUCCAGGUGUUUUUGGUGGUAUAGGCGAUCCUGUUACCUGCCUUAAGAGUGGAGCCAUAUGUCAUCCAGUCUUUUGCCCUAGAAGGUAUAAACAAAUUGGCACCUGUGGUCUCCCUGGAACAAAAUGCUGCAAAAAGCCAUGAGGAGGCCAAGAAGCUGCUGUGGCUGAUGCGGAUUCAGAAAGGGCUCCCUCAUCAGAGACGUGCGACAUGUAAACCAAAUUAAACUAUGGUGUCCAAAGAUACGCAA